CUUCUCUUUAGGCGGGAAUAGCCUUGUUCUCAUUAUGUGGUUUUUAAAAUGCUUAGCUAUAUGCCAACAGCCUGGGAAAGUGCCCCAGAAGGGUGUGCCAAGCAUCAAGCCUGAGUGGGUGACUGUGACGGGGUUGGAGGCUGGUGCACACAGGGAGUCAGGGCCUCCCCACCCCAGCCUUGAGUGGGAGACACACAAGUCCUACGUGACUUAUUUCUGUAUUUUCAGUAUGAGCUUAGUGCUCUCUCCUUGGCCUCUCCAGGGAAAGAUUAUUUAGACUCAUAUUCAGAAUCAUCAAAAUUCCCUUCUCUCCAAACACCAGCCCUGGCCUGGAGACCAAGGCUACCAUUGGGGUUUAGUGGAAAGGAUUGUGGACUUGACGUCAGAAGAUGUGAUUUUUUUCUGUGUCCCUGAUGAGUGGCAUGACCUUAAUCAAGUCAUGUCCACUCUCUCUGUCUCUUUUUCUUUCUCUACAAAACAAUGAGGGCUCUCACUCUUCAAGAACAAUGUUGCCUGAGUCUGUGGCCCAUCCUGCCAUAGUUCCCGGGACACAGAAGGCACUCAGUAUUGCUGAGAUUUGCCGACUCUAAAAUCUGACGAGGCCGCAGUGCCUUGGUGGGAGGGCUCCCCACUUUCUCUCUCUGGGAGCGUGUCUGUCUGUGCUCAGACAUGUAUGAAGCACAGAUCCUGGCCUGUAAAUCCAUCCCUGAAUCCUGGGCUUCCACUUGGAUGGCAGCUUGUGAGUCUGGAGAUCGAAUCUGCUGAAUAAUUAGAAAGUCGCCCCCGGUCUUUGUGGAUUAGUAUCCUUUAUCAAAUGAUGGCUCUUUCACACCCAGGCCCUCCCCCAGUGAACCUCAUUGGCAGCAUCUUAAAAACAGGAAGACUGAGGCUGCAAAGGGUGAAGGGCCUGCCCAAGGUCCUGUGGUGUGUAGAGCGGUGUCCCCUAAAAAUGUUUGUCCACCAGGAACUUGGGAAUGUGACCUCACUUGGGAAUAGGGCCUGUGCAGAUGCGAUUGGUUGGGAGGAGGUCACACUGCAUUAGGGUGGGUUCCCGUAAGGGUAGAGGCCGCACAGAGACACAGAGAAGCCAUGUGCCGACUGAGGCAGAGACUGGAGUGAUGUAGCCACAAGCCAAGGGACGCCUGGGGCCACCGGAAACUGGAAGAAGCCAGGAAGGACCCUUCCCAGGAGCUUUCGGGGAGAGCACAGCCCUGCCAACACCUUGAUUUUGAACCUCUAGUCUCCAGAAAUGGGAGGCAAUACAUUUCUGUUGUUUGAAACCAAUCUAGUCCCCUAACCAGGCUGGCGGAGCAGGGACCUGAACCCACCUCUGUCCUGCUCCAUGCUGCCUGGGUUCAUGCUGGGCAGCCCCACUUCCUGUGGGAGCCAGCGUUGACCUCACAUCUACGCCCCGACCCUAAGCAGGCUGUGUCCUGCCCUUCCAUGGCCCAUGCUCUCAGCCUGACACCGAGGGGGUGGAGGGGACUCUCUCAGUGAUGAGUGACCAGUCACUGCUCUGAAGUGGCCGAGGUCCCUCUUGGGGCAAAUGCAUGAGGCCCCCUUGCCCGCGUUGGUCCUCCCCAGUGAAACGUGCCCAUAGGCACAGGUCCGCAGAGAGAAGGAAACGCAAGGACCCGUUCAGAAGUCGGUGUGACUCACUCUGACGUCAGCAACCUGCAGUGGGUCUUUCCCAGGCCACACUCACUCGCAUGGCAAGGCGGUCCUCCCCGACUGCUAAAAACAAAAGUCAGGAAAGGAAUUUCCCCACCACCUACACACUCAUGCUGCUCCCCACCACCUACACACUCAUGCUGCUCUGGGCUGUGCAGCCUCAGUGCCCCAGCUUUCCUAGAGACCGUGGGAGCUUCCCAUUUGCCUCUAAAGGCUCACCUCUCACGUGGGAGACAGCAGUGAGCCCCAACUUCGGGGCUCCAGGGAAAGGCUUGCAUCAACCUUGACCUUUUUUAGGGGGUGAGCAGAUCCUGUUUGUAAGUGCCCUGCCGUGGAGUGGGGGCAGGGUACGUCUGUGCACCGACACGGCGUCUCUAGCAGGAAACUUUAGGUUAGGAGGCUGAUUUCCCACUGCAGCCUUGGCGAGCAGGCGCUGCCGUCCUCCAGCAGAUGCUGCUGAAGCAGAAAUUGGGCAGGCCCAGAGGCUCAGUCAAGGUCACCCUGCAAAAGGGGGCAAAGUGCAGCCUAAAACUAGGUCUAUCUGACACCAAAGUUUGUGUUGUUCCCGUCAAGACACAGACCGCCUCCCUAGGACAUAAAAUACUUUGUGGCUCAACUGAAAUCAGAUCCUGGCUGCUUUGGUGAUGCCAGCUGCUCUGCUCAGACUGACCUGAGAGCCCCUGGCAGGACCAGGGAGGGCUAGGGCCACAGGGGCAGAGGACACCCAAAAAGACCUGAGGCUCAACCACUCCCAGGACUUCCUGCUUCACCAAAACAAGGUGAACCUUAAAGACACUGUGUGUUUUAUAGUUUUGUUGCCUAAAGAGUUUUCUUCUUGAAACUCUACGAUUAAACAAAAAGCCGUUGAACUGGAGCUCGGGCCUGCAAGUCCAGGCCACUGGGUAACGUGCACACCCCGGGGAAUGGAGGAGCCGUUUACUCUGUGCAUCUGAAUCGUGCAUUCGGGCAGCUAGCCUGCAAACCGAUAGGCCCCCGAGACCCUGAACCCACAUCUCCAUAUCGUCCUCUUUCCUACUUCCUGGAAAAAUCUACAGGGAUCCAGCCAUCUCCUUUAUGAUACUGCUCCGUGAAGCCUUGCACCAAACAGCUGCAUCUGACCUUGGCCCACAAGUUCUACCCCCACCACCAGAGGACGCUGGAGCAGCUGGCCAGAGCCAUCCCCCUGGGCCACAGCUGCCAGUGGACCGCAGCACUCUACUCCCGAGACAUGCGCUUUGUGCACUACCAGACCCUGAGAGCCCUAUUCCAGUACAAACCCCAGAACGUGGAUGAGCUGACGCUAAGUCCUGGUGACUACAUCUUUGUGGACCCCACGCAGCAGGACGAAGCCAGCGAGGGCUGGGUGAUUGGGAUCUCACAGCGGACGGGCUGCCGGGGCUUCCUGCCGGAAAACUACACGGAUCGAGCCAGUGAGUCUGACACGUGGGUGAAGCACAGGAUGUACACCUUCAGUCUAGCCACAGACCUGAACUCCAGAAAGGAUGGUGAAGCCAGCAGCAGAUGCAGCGGGGAAUUUCUUCCACAAACGGCAAGGAGUCUUAGCAGCUUACAGGCCUUGCAGGCUACCGUUGCAAGGAAGAGCGUGCUGGUGGUUCGCCACGGGGAGAGAGUGGAUCAGAUCUUCGGGAAGGCAUGGCUGCAGCAAUGCUCCACUCCUGAUGGGAAAUACUACAGGCCAGACCUGAAUUUCCCCUGCAGUCUGCCAAGACGGAGUCGUGGGAUCAAAGACUUUGAAAACGAUCCCCCAUUAUCAUCGUGUGGCAUUUUCCAGUCCAGAAUUGCAGGUAUGUUUGAGGACUGUCUAGUAGGAAAGGGGACGCGCUACUGGACAGUGGUAUCAGAAUCAGCUCUGUGUUUGCCUCCCCAGCCCUCCGCUGUGUGCAGACGGCCAAACUCAUCCUGGAAGGUCAGUGAGAACCUCGAACUCAAACUGGAGAAAAAAAUCAAGAUACGAGUGGAACCUGGAAUCUUUGAAUGGACAAAAUGGGAAGCUGGCAAAACCACCCCAACCCUCAUGAGCCUGGAAGAGCUGAAAGAGGCAAAUUUCAACAUUGACACUGAUUACAGGCCCGCGUUUCCCCUGUCCGCCCUCAUGCCGGCCGAGAGCUACCAGGAGUACAUGGACAGGUGCACGGCGAGCAUGGUGCAAAUCGUCAACACCUGUCCACAGGACACGGGUGUCAUCCUAAUUGUGAGUCACGGCUCCACUCUGGACUCCUGCACGCGGCCACUGCUCGGGCUGCCGCCCCGGGAAUGUGGGGAUUUUGCCCAACUCGUGAGAAAGAUCCCUUCCCUGGGCAUGUGCUUCUGUGAAGAAAAUAAAGAGGAAGGAAAAUGGGAGUUGGUGAACCCACCGGUGAAGACCCUGACCCACGGGGCGAACGCAGCAUUUAACUGGAGGAACUGGAUCUCAGGCAACUGAGAGCCACGGUGAUGUUGUCAUAACCUCAGAGUGGAGAGGCAGAAACCAUGUGCAGAGGCUGGGAGAUGCUGCUGUUUCCAGAGGCGUCUUAGUCUCACCCAAUGUGAUUUGUAGAAGCACGAGACGCACUUUUAUAUCCCGGAAUAUUUCCCUCCGGCUUUCGCCUUUGUAACUCCCAUCUGUGGACCCAUCGUCCACCAGCCCAGCUGCGGGGAGCACAGGGCAGGUGGCUGGGUGAGGAUGCCGCCCUGCAGCAUGUACACCGAGUGUCUGCAGCUGGGGACACAACUGCCCGGGACUCUAACUUCCAGGAAUUAAAGACUCACCACACACGAAGGAUCUAACCACUUCAUUUUCCAUGGUCUAAUCAUUAAAUUCCCAAUCGUUUUUUCUUUUUCUGGGUCCAUCACUCUUUAGCCAUAUCCACAUGGGCUAAAACAGGUGUAAUAGUCAAUAAAAUGGUCCCAGAAAACCAUCGACCAGGUCAAAA